GCAUUUUUCUCCAGCGAGAGGAAGGAUGACUCCUAGACCUGUCUUUGUCCCAUACUUGGGAAGAUAAGCUGUUAGUUUACAUUGCCAAGAUGAAAUUCAACUGAUCUGUUUUAGAGUAAAGAUCUUGCGGGCCAACAAGGAAUUUCCUUGGGGAGGUGUGUGGCCUUUGAUCUUUGUAGCUAUUUAGCAACAAAAUGGGAGGCAGUGUUGCCUGACUCAGUUUCCAAGCUUGACUCUUCCCUUUGGCAUAGUGAGUUUGGAGUCAAGAGAUUUUUAUUUUCCCUUCACAAGCUGAACAGGAGCCUUUGGAGAGAACGCUCUGGACCGGAAGCGCGCCCCCGGGGCCGGUCCCGGAGGGCUCGAUCCGCAUCUACAGCAUGAGGUUCUGCCCGUUUGCUGAGAGGACGCGUCUAGUCCUGAAGGCCAAGGGAAUCAGGCAUGAAGUCAUCAAUAUCAACCUGAAAAAUAAGCCUGAGUGGUUCUUUAAGAAAAAUCCCUUUGGUCUGGUGCCAGUUCUGGAAAACAGUCAGGGUCAGCUGAUCUACGAGUCUGCCAUCACCUGUGAGUACCUGGAUGAAGCAUACCCAGGGAAGAAGCUGUUGCCGGAUGACCCCUAUGAGAAAGCUUGCCAGAAGAUGAUCUUAGAGUUGUUUUCUAAGGUGCCAUCCUUGGUAGGAAGCUUUAUUAGAAGCCAAAAUAAAGAAGACUAUGCUGGCCUAAAAGAAGAAUUUCGUAAAGAAUUUACCAAGCUAGAGGAGGUUCUGACUAAUAAGAAGACGACCUUCUUUGGUGGCAAUUCUAUCUCUAUGAUUGAUUACCUCAUCUGGCCCUGGUUUGAACGGCUGGAAGCAAUGAAGUUAAAUGAGUGUGUAGACCACACUCCAAAACUGAAACUGUGGAUGGCAGCCAUGAAGGAAGAUCCCACAGUCUCAGCCCUGCUUACUAGUGAGAAAGACUGGCAAGGUUUCCUAGAGCUCUACUUACAGAACAGCCCUGAGGCCUGUGACUAUGGGCUCUGAAGGGGGCAGGAGUCAGCAAUAAAGCUAUGUCUGAUAUUUUCCUUCACUAA